GCCUCCCUCGCUCCACGCGCGCCCGGACUCGGCGGCCAGGCUUGCGCGCGGUUCCCCUCCCGGUGGGCGGAUUCCUGGGCAAGAUGAAGUGGGUGUGGGCGCUCUUGCUGUUGGCGGCGCUGGGCAGCGGCCGCGCGGAGCGCGACUGCCGAGUGAGCAGCUUCCGAGUCAAGGAGAACUUCGACAAGGCUCGCUUCUCUGGGACCUGGUACGCCAUGGCCAAGAAGGACCCCGAGGGCCUCUUUCUGCAGGACAACAUCGUCGCGGAGUUCUCCGUGGACGAGACCGGCCAGAUGAGCGCCACAGCCAAGGGCCGAGUCCGUCUUUUGAAUAACUGGGACGUGUGCGCAGACAUGGUGGGCACCUUCACAGACACCGAGGACCCUGCCAAGUUCAAGAUGAAGUACUGGGGCGUAGCCUCCUUUCUCCAGAAAGGAAAUGAUGACCACUGGAUCGUCGACACAGACUACGACACGUAUGCCGUGCAGUACUCCUGCCGCCUCCUGAACCUCGAUGGCACCUGUGCUGACAGCUACUCCUUCGUGUUUUCCCGGGACCCCAACGGCCUGCCCCCAGAAGCGCAGAAGAUUGUAAGGCAGCGGCAGGAGGAGCUGUGCCUGGCCAGGCAGUACAGGCUGAUCGUCCACAACGGUUACUGCGAUGGCAGAUCAGAAAGAAACCUUUUGUAGCAAUAUCAAGAAUCUAGUUUCAUCUGAGAACUUCUGAUUAGCUCUCAGUCUUCAGCUCUAUUUAUCUUAGGAGUUUAAUUUGCCCUUCUCUCCCCAUCUUCCCUCAGUUCCCAUAAAACCUUCAUUACACAUAAAGAUACACGUGGGGGUCAGUGAAUCUGCUUGCCUUUCCUGAAAGUUUCUGGGGCUUAAGAUUCCAGACUCUGAUUCAUUAAACUAUAGUCACCCGUGUCCUGUGAUUUUAGUUUUCAUUUGUGUUUAUGUCUGUGCUGCAGACGGAUGGGUGGGGUGCGCUUCUUUAUACCAGGAGCACGUGGCUCUUUCUGACCUUUGGCCUGUUCUAGUGCCUAAUCUCCAUUAUUAAAUACUGGCUUCUCCCAA